GGACCGCGCGCACAGCCCGCACUGCCCCACGCCGCGGGCUAGGGACACCCGGCCCGCCACCAUGACUUCCAGCAAGAUAGAGAUGCCCGGCGAGGUGAAGGCCGACCCCGCCGCCCUCAUGGCGUCGCUGCACCUCCUGCCGUCGCCCACGCCCAAUCUCGAAAUUAAGUACACCAAGGUGUGAAAAUUGGACUUGCUGGCAGAAUCCUUUUUGGGAGAAGAUGAAGAAUCAGUGUGAGACUGUUUGGUUAAAAUCCCCAAUAAAACUGAAACUGAUCUUUAUAAACAACGAGUGGCAGAACUCAGAGAGUGGGAGAGUGUUCCCUGUCUAUAAUCCAGCCACAGGAGAACAGGUGUGUGAAGUUCAAGAAGCAGACAAGGCAGAUAUAGACAAAGCAGUGCAGGCAGCCCGCCUGGCUUUCUCUCUUGGUUCAGUGUGGAGAAGGAUGGAUGCUUCAGAAAGGGGACGUCUGUUGGAUAAGCUUGCAGACUUGGUGGAACGGGACAGGGCAGUUCUUGCAACCAUGGAAUCCCUAAAUGGUGGCAAACCAUUCCUGCAAGCUUUUUAUGUGGAUUUGCAGGGCGUCAUCAAAACCUUUCGAUAUUACGCAGGCUGGGCUGAUAAAAUUCAUGGGAUGACCAUUCCUGUAGAUGGAGACUAUUUUACCUUUACAAGACAUGAACCCAUUGGAGUGUGUGGACAGAUCAUCCCAUGGAACUUCCCCCUGCUGAUGUUUGCCUGGAAAAUAGCUCCAGCUUUGUGCUGUGGCAAUACAGUAGUUAUUAAGCCAGCAGAGCAAACACCACUCAGUGCACUCUACAUGGGAGCCCUCAUCAAGGAGGCUGGCUUUCCUCCCGGGGUCAUCAAUAUUUUGCCAGGAUAUGGGCCAACGGCUGGGGCAGCAAUAGCUUCUCACAUUGGCAUAGACAAGAUUGCAUUCACAGGGUCUACUGAGGUUGGAAAGCUUAUCCAAGAAGCAGCUGGAAGAAGUAAUUUGAAGAGAGUAACUCUGGAACUUGGAGGCAAAAGUCCUAAUAUUAUUUUUGCUGAUGCUGACUUGGACUAUGCUGUGGAGCAGGCCCACCAGGGUGUGUUCUUCAAUCAAGGUCAGUGCUGCACUGCAGGCUCUCGCAUCUUCGUGGAGGAGUCCAUCUAUGAGGAGUUUGUGAGAAGAAGCGUGGAGCGGGCCAAGAGGCGCGUAGUGGGGAGUCCCUUUGACCCCACCACUGAGCAGGGUCCCCAGAUUGAUAAGAAACAGUACAACAAGAUCUUGGAACUCAUCCAGAGUGGUGUGGCUGAGGGCGCCAAGCUGGAAUGUGGAGGCAAAGGACUGGGCCGAAAGGGGUUUUUCAUUGAGCCCACAGUGUUUUCCAACGUCACUGAUGAUAUGCGGAUUGCCAAGGAGGAGAUCUUUGGCCCUGUUCAGGAAAUUUUGAGAUUUAAGACGAUGGAUGAAGUUAUCGAAAGAGCCAAUAACUCAGACUUUGGACUCGUAGCAGCUGUCUUUACUAAUGACAUCAACAAGGCCCUCACAGUGUCUUCUGCAAUGCAAGCUGGGACUGUUUGGAUCAAUUGUUACAAUGCCUUAAAUGCCCAGAGCCCCUUUGGGGGAUUCAAGAUGUCUGGAAAUGGGAGAGAAAUGGGAGAAUUUGGCUUGCGGGAGUACUCAGAAGUUAAGACGGUGACAGUAAAGAUCCCCCAGAAGAACUCCUAAGAAGGCCAAGAAGGAGGAUGAAGCCCAGCCUGCACGUCUGUCCCUCUCUGCUUUCUCUGUAGGGCCCAGCUCUCAGGAAUACAAAGUUGAGCCACGGUCCUUACUUAAAGAUUGAAAAGAUAACAUGUAGGCCAGGCAGGUCACUGCACAACUAAAGCAAACCAGCUGGGUACAGUUUCUUGGCACUCUGUAAGGGGCCACCUUAAUCAUACCAAAUAUUGGGGAAAGUGGGAUAAAGGGAGGAGGAGGAGCUAGCAGACACAUCCAGUAUCUCCUUCUGGAGCACAGGAUGAAAUAAGGGAGCUGUAUUAUUUCAUGUCUUUGUCACAAAGAACUUUCCUCUCAAGGAAAGGUGACCUUUCUCCUGUCUUCAUUUUCCUCCUUCCAGGCCCUCCUCGCUCACCCACCCCUCCCUCUCUUCCAAGGAGAUGUCAGCUGAGCUCAUUCUGGGGCAGAUGUUUGGGCCGGGAACAAUUUUUCAAGGUUGUAAAGCCAAAUUAUCAUUUCAUGUUAUCCAUUUCUUCAAAGCAAAACAUGAAAUGGUUUUAGCUAGAGUCAGACCAGAAUGAAAAUGCCAGGAGCUGGUACACUACAGAUGUAGUAAGAACCUGGGAUAUUCCUGACCCAAUCUGGUUUUCUUUUACCCAUAAAUAACAUGAAUGAAAAAAGAUUGGGACAAUAGAGACUGGAAGUCAUCAUGUGCAGUUCACCGCUUCUGAGCUUGCUGCAGUUUUGGGGUGUGUGUGUAUUAGAUUCCUUCUCAGUUAUUCUGGAAUAAGGCAAGGAGUGGGUUGUUUUUCAUAGCUAGAUAAGAUCUUUUCCAAAGUUUUUCUUAGAACCAACCAAAAAACAAUCCGAGUAGGCCCAAGAAUUUGAUAAUGCUGGAUGCCUUGCAGACAUCAUUCAGUUUCUAAUAUUGGGCAACAAUUAUUAUUAAAUGAAUUAUUUCUGUAGUUGGAAUCUGUACCUUCUGAACCUCUACACCAAUAACUGCUGCAGGUGUGAUUUUGGUCUGUCACACUGUACAUCUAUCAUAAUGUGCCCUGUAUCUAUUGGCAGUGACCUUGGAAAAUCUGGCCAAGCCUAGGGGUUUCCUUUUCCAUUUGCCAAGUUCCAUUGUGCCAGGACUGCCGUGCUCCACUGAGCUCCUCUGUCACACCCCAUUCUUGCCCCUCACUGGGCAGGCCAUGGCCUACAGCUUGCAGGGAGUAAAGCAGGCCCGCCUCCCUUUCUUCCCAUCCACAUACUCCUCUUCUGCUUUCCAGUGACUCCACCAGUUUGAUGUGGGAAGUGUUAGCUUCCUUUCCUUCUUCCAUCCCUUCUUCCAUCUUUCCAGCUGUCAAAUCCAAUCCAGUCUCUAACCUAAAUGCAGAUCAUUUAUUUAAAAGUACCAAACAUAACCCAGAGUAUGUGGAAUAUGGGCAACAUAUAUAUAGCCUUCUGUAUUUAACGAUCUUCUGCUUCUUAACCGUACCAGUUUUCUAUUUAUAACUCUUAUCUAUCCAUGAUGUUUUAAAGUCUCCACUUGCUGUUAUUUACAAACGACAGUGCAUUCAGCAGCCCAGUGCCGUGAGCCCUGACAGAUGCCGUAUUUCUGAGUGCUUCCAUGUGAAUGCUGCCCUCCUGUAGCAUGUGUCCAAGUGGACAUAGCCACUAACCAACUAGUUACCUUUGGACUGCAACAAAAAAUGUGAAAAUGAAGAUUUAUUUCUUUUAAUUUACUUAAAAAGAAACCUCUGUGCUAGCAAUAAAGCAUUUAUAUUGUGUA